GAGAAGAAAUUUCCUGACAGCCGAAGAGCAACAAGUAUCAUGAUGGGGUGCUGGAUUUUGAAUGAGGGUCUCUCCACCAUAUUAGUACUCUCAUGGCUGGGAAUAAAUUUUUAUCUGUUUAUUGACACGUUCUACUGGUAUGAAGAGGAGGAGUCUUUCCAUUACACACGAGUUAUUUUGGGUUCAACACUGGCUUGGGCACGAGCAUCCGCACUGUGCCUGAAUUUUAACUGCAUGCUAAUUCUAAUACCUGUCAGUCGAAACCUUAUUUCAUUCAUAAGAGGAACAAGUAUUUGCUGCAGAGGACCGUGGAGGAGGCAAUUAGACAAAAACCUCAGAUUUCACAAACUGGUCGCCUAUGGGAUAGCUGUUAAUGCAACCAUCCACAUCGUGGCGCAUUUCUUCAACCUGGAACGCUACCACUGGAGCCAGUCCGAGGAGGCCCAGGGACUUCUGGCCGCACUUUCCAAGCUGGGCAACACCCCUAACGAGAGCUACCUCAACCCUGUCCGGACCUUCCCCACAAACACAACCACUGAAUUGCUAAGGACAAUAGCAGGCGUCACCGGUCUGGUGAUCUCUCUGGCUUUAGUCUUGAUCAUGACCUCGUCAACUGAGUUCAUCAGACAGGCCUCCUAUGAGUUGUUCUGGUACACACACCAUGUUUUCAUCGUCUUCUUUCUCAGCCUGGCCAUCCAUGGGACGGGUCGGAUUGUUCGAGGCCAAACCCAAGACAGUCUCUCUCUGCACAACAUCACCUUCUGUAGAGACCGCUAUGCAGAAUGGCAGACAGUGGCCCAAUGCCCCGUGCCUCAAUUUUCUGGCAAGGAACCCUCGGCUUGGAAAUGGAUUUUAGGCCCUGUGGUCUUGUAUGCAUGUGAAAGAAUAAUUAGGUUCUGGCGAUUUCAACAAGAAGUUGUCAUUACCAAGGUGGUAAGCCACCCCUCUGGAGUCCUGGAACUUCACAUGAAAAAGCGUGGCUUUAAAAUGGCGCCAGGGCAGUACAUCUUGGUGCAGUGCCCAGCCAUAUCUUCGCUGGAGUGGCACCCCUUCACCCUUACCUCUGCCCCCCAGGAGGACUUUUUCAGCGUGCACAUCCGGGCAGCAGGAGACUGGACAGCAGCGCUACUGGAGGCCUUUGGGGCAGAGGGACAGGCCCUCCAGGAGCCCUGGAGCCUGCCAAGGCUGGCAGUGGACGGGCCCUUUGGAACUGCCCUGACAGAUGUAUUUCACUACCCAGUGUGUGUGUGCGUUGCCGCGGGGAUCGGAGUCACUCCCUUCGCUGCUCUUCUGAAAUCUAUAUGGUACAAAUGCAGUGAGGCACAGACCCCACUGAAGCUGAGCAAGGUGUAUUUCUACUGGAUUUGCCGGGAUGCAAGAGCUUUUGAGUGGUUUGCUGAUCUCUUACUCUCCCUGGAAACACGGAUGAGUGAGCAGGGGAAAACUCACUUUCUGAGUUAUCAUAUAUUUCUUACCGGCUGGGAUGAAAAUCAGGCUCUUCACAUAGCUUUACACUGGGACGAAAAUACUGACGUGAUUACAGGCUUAAAGCAGAAGACCUUCUAUGGGAGGCCCAACUGGAACAAUGAGUUCAAGCAGAUUGCCUACAAUCACCCCAGCAGCAGUAUUGGCGUGUUCUUCUGUGGACCUAAAGCUCUCUCGAGGACACUUCAAAAGAUGUGCCACUUGUAUUCAUCAGCUGACCCCAGAGGUGUUCAUUUCUAUUACAACAAGGAGAGCUUCUAGACUUUGGAGGUCAAGUCCAGGCAUUGUGUUUUCAAUCAAGUUAUUGAUUCCAAAGAACUCCACCAGGAAUUCCUGUGACGGCCUGUUGAUAUGAGCUCCCAGUUGGGAACUGGUGAAUAAUAAUUAACUAUUGUGAACAGUACACUAUACCAUACUUCCUUAGCUUAUAAAUAACAUGUCAUAUACAACAGAACAAAAACAUUUACUGAAAUUAAAAUAUAUUAUGUUUCUCAA